GGAUGGUUUCCAUAAGGGAUUUUACCAUGCCUAAGAAGUUUGUCCAGAUGCUGGUUUUUAAUUUGACUCUGACUGAAGUUGUUCUAAGUGGGAAUGUGUUAAUUUGGCCUACAGAUGGUAGCCAUUGGUUAAAUAUUAAGAUUAUUCUAGAAGAGUUGAUUCAAAGAAAUCACAAUGUGACUGUACUGGCUUCAUCAGCAACUCUAUUCAUCAACUCCAAUCCCGAUUCUCCUGUGAAUUUUGAAGUGAUACCUGUUUCCUACAAGAAGAGCAAUAUAGAUUCCUUAAUUGAGCAUAUGAUAAUGCUGUGGAUUGACCAUAGACCAACUCCUCUCACAAUAUGGGCUUUCUACAAAGAACUAGGAAAACUUCUAGACACUUUCUUUCAAAUUAACAUACAACUCUGUGAUGGUGUACUAAAGAACCCAAAGUUGAUGGCAAGACUUCAGAAAGGUGGUUUUGAUGUGUUGGUAGCAGACCCAGUAACAAUCUGUGGUGAUCUUGUUGCUCUGAAAUUAGGAAUUCCAUUUAUGUACACAUUGAGGUUCUCUCCAGCAUCAACAGUGGAGAGACACUGUGGGAAAAUCCCAGCACCAGUCUCCUAUGUACCGGCAGCCUUAUCAGAGCUCACUGACCAGAUGACCUUUGGUGAAAGGAUUAAAAAUACCAUAUCUUAUUCUCUGCAAGACUAUAUAUUUCAGUCCUACUGGGGAGAAUGGAAUUCAUACUAUAGCAAAAUUUUAGGAAGACCCACUACGUUAUGUGAGACUAUGGGGAAAGCUGAAAUUUGGUUAAUCCGAACAUAUUGGGAUUUUGAAUUUCCUCGUCCAUACUUACCUAAUUUUGAGUUUGUUGGAGGAUUGCACUGCAAACCUGCCAAACCUUUACCUAAGGAAAUGGAAGAAUUUAUCCAGAGCUCAGGUAAAAAUGGUGUUGUGGUGUUUUCUCUGGGAUCAAUGGUCAAAAACCUUACAGAAGAAAAGGCCAAUCUUAUUGCCUCAGCCCUUGCCCAGAUUCCACAGAAGGUUUUAUGGAGAUACAAAGGAAAGAAACCAGCCACAUUAGGAAACAAUACUCAGCUCUUUGAUUGGAUACCCCAGAAUGAUCUUCUUGGACAUCCCAAAACCAAAGCUUUUAUCACUCAUGGUGGAACUAAUGGGAUCUACGAAGCUAUUUACCACGGAGUCCCUAUGGUGGGAGUUCCCAUGUUUGCUGAUCAGCCUGAUAACAUUGCUCACAUGAAGGCCAAAGGAGCAGCUGUGGAAGUGAACCUAAACACAAUGACAAGUGUGGAUUUGCUUAGCGCUUUGAGAACAGUCAUUAAUGAACCUUCUUAUAAAGAGAAUGCUAUGAGGUUAUCAAGAAUUCACCAUGAUCAACCUGUAAAGCCCCUGGAUCGAGCAGUCUUCUGGAUCGAGUUUGUCAUGCGCCACAAAGGAGCCAAGCACCUUCGGGUUGCAGCCCAUGACCUCACCUGGUUCCAGUACCACUCUUUGGAUGUAAUUGGGUUCUUGCUGGUCUGUGUGACAACGGCUAUAUUUUUGGUCAUACAAUGUUGUUUGUUUUCCUGUCAAAAAUUUGGUAAGAUAGGAAAGAAGAAAAAAAGAGAAUAGGUCAAGAAAAAGAGGAAAUAUAUAUAUUUUUAAGUUUGGCAAAAUCCUGAGUAGUGUAGUCCUAUUAAUUCCAGACAAAAGGAGUUUAACAAAAACACGUCUCCCAUCCUGUUUCCAAAUUUUCUAUUUCUCUACCUGCGAUAAGCCUACUGAUAAAGCCUAGAUUUUGGCAUGAUUAUUAUUAACUUGUGAGUUAUAGUCUUCUAUUUUUCCUUUGUCUCUCCCUGCUGACUAUACCCUCUUCCUGUCACUUUUCUGACACAAGGAUACUACCUAAUUUUAAAUAUGUUCUAUUCAUAGUAUCAAAUUAUUUUAUCGUUAACCUUAAUUAAUGAUUAACAAUAUGCUGAAUCCUGGUAAUGCAUACAGUGUAGAUGGAAUUUGAUAGGUGUAAGGAAGAGUCAAAUUCACAAAUUUCCAUAUACCAAACAAAUCAGGGAGCCACCGUAGGAGAGUAGUGUGUUAUGAGAAAGGUAAUGAUUUCCUUUUUUAAUAAAAACAAACUCUUCUGCUUGCUCAAUGUUUCAGGAGUUAGAGAAUGAAUUUUAAGUGUGACGUGCGUCCCUAUUAAAUGUCUACAAAAUUUUCAUUAAGCAUAUCUAGAAAAUCACGGCAUAACUUGCCUGCCUUUCUUCAACAUAUAUUCUUAUAUAACCUGUAGUGGAAGAUUUGGGUACUGUCUUUAAUAAAUCAAUCAAUCGACUCUUUUAUUUCAAGGAGAAAGUUCUAUGUUAUAUGUUGAAGGUGAACAGAUCAUAUUUAGAGGAUAUAACAAUUAGAAAUCUAGAAAAUAAUUAUCAUUUUUAUAAAAUUUUUAGUCAACUGUACAAAUAAUUACAUAAAACAUCAAUUAAUUAUGCUUAAAAAUCACUAAUGUUCAUAAUAUAUAAUCACUAUUUGUAAUCAAAAGUUUAAUUUUAUGCCAAAAAAUAAAAAAUGCUUACUUGGAAUUUGA